ACAGGGUCCUGCUCUGUUGCCUAGCUGGAGUGCAGUGCCACCCCCUCCCAGGCUCAGUCGAUCCUUCCACAUCAGCCACCCCUGACCCUGUCUACCCCUGCCCCGGAGUAGCUGGGACUACAGGUGCGUAUGCCACCACGCCUGGGUAAUUUUUGUAUUUUUUGUAGAGACAUGGUUUCACCAUGUUGCCUAUGAUGGUCUUGAACUUUCUGGCCUCAAGCGAUCGGCCCACUUUAGCCUUCCAAAGUGCUGGGAUUACAGGUGUGAACCACUGUGUCUGGCUUUAAGUUUAUUUUUCAACUCCUGUUACUUCGUUUACGGCAUUAACUUGUAAAUUUGUCACUAACCCACAAUCUUUCCCUGGGCUCAAGACCCAUAUAUACCACUCCUUACCUUAAAAUUCAUGUGUCCCCAACUGAACUUGCGUUGGAUAGUAUUAAAUAGGACUUGUAUUACCCAGUUUAUCUUAGAUUCUGCAUUUGAAUUUGUAACCCCAGGGAAAUGGCCCUUUCCUACAUCUCCAGCCCUUUUUAAUGUCUAUGCACAGGAGGCUGAGGCGGAAGGAUUGCUUAAACCCGGGACGCAGAGGUUGCAGUGAGCCAUGGUCACACCACUGCACUCCAGCCUGAGCAACAGAGCAAGACCCUGUCUCCAAAAAUAAACAACACACCAAAAAUUCUGCAGUUUCCCAAAGUCUACCUCAGAGUUUUCACACAUUCUGAUCCCUCUGCCUGGGGAUGCUUUAUUCCCUUCACCUAGUUAAUUGCCUACUCGUCAGAUAUUAGCUCAAACCUCAGUUUCUCAGGAAAGCUCCUCAUUCCCUCAGAUUAUUCACUCGUCUCAAAUACAUAUUUAUUGGUUUAAUGUCUGCAUAAAGUGUAAGCUCCAUGAGGGCAGUGCCUUUGUCUCCUUUCCUGCUCUUUGGCUGAGGCCUAAUAUAUUGACACAGUAGGUACUCAAGAAAUAUUUCUUGUAUCACUGACUAAAUUAGAUUGAGAUAAAGUAAUAUUGUGAAUCAGUGGCUUACUACUUAUUUUGUAGAUAAAACAAUUUACCCUGUCUUGAGAUGGUAACUUCAUUUUUUUUUGAAACGGAGUUUUGCUUUUGUUGCCCAGGCUGGCGUGCAAUGGCGCGACCUUGGCUUCACCGCAACCUCCGCCUCCCGGGUUCAAGCGAUUCUCCUGCCUCAGCCUCUCGAGUAGCUGGGAUUACUGGUAUGCACCACCAUGCCCGGUUAAUUUUUGUAUUUCGAGUAGAGACGGGGUUUCUCCAUGUUGGUCAGGCUAGUCUCGAACUCCCGACCUCAAGUGAUCCACCUGCCUCGGGUUUCCAAAGUGCUGGGAUUACAGGCAUGAGUCACCGCGCCUGGCCAAGUAACUUCAUUUUUAUGGCUAUGCCAUUUCAGGUAGUGCUUCGUUGAGGCAUCAAGACUCCACUGACCAGCUUUUUCACUUUAUUGAAUUACAUAACCUUUUUUUUUUUUUUUUUUUUUUUUUUGAGACAAUGUCUGACUCUGUAGCCCAGGCUGGAGUGUGCAGUGGUGCACUAGGCUCACGGCAACCUCCGCCUCCGGCUCAAACGAUCCUCAGCCCCGUCCUCCGUACCAGAGUUGUCUGCUGGUUCUCAGCUUGAAGAAGAUUCUGCAGUCCUUAUUGAUCCUUUUUCUUGGCGUUACCAUUUUUGAAGCAAAGUUAACCUAGCUUUCUAGUUUGAGCUUUCUUUUUGGCCGUCUUUAAAAAAAUUUUUUUUUUUAAUCUAUAAAAUAGACAAGAGCUAGUUCUACAAUGUCCAAGUCAUUCCAGCAGUCAUCUCUCAGUAGGGACUCACAGGGUCAUGGGCGUGACCUGUCUGCGGCAGGAAUAGGCCUUCUUGCUGCUGCUACCCAGUCUUUAAGUAUGCCAGCAUCUCUUGGAAGGAUGAACCAGGGUACUGCACGCCUUGCUAGUUUAAUGAAUCUUGGAAUGAGUUCUUCAUUGAAUCAACAAGGAGCUCAUAGUGCACUGUCUUCUGCUAGUACUUCUUCCCAUAAUUUGCAGUCUAUAUUUAACAUUGGAAGUAGAGGUCCACUCCCUUUAUCUUCUCAACACCGUGGAGAUGCAGACCAGGCCAGUAACAUUUUGGCCAGCUUUGGUCUGUCUGCUAGAGACUUAGAUGAACUGAGUCGUUAUCCAGAGGACAAGAUUACUCCUGAGAAUUUGCCCCAAAUCCUUCUACAGCUUAAAAGGAGGAGAACUGAAGAAGGCCCUACCUUGAGUUAUGGUAGAGAUGGCAGAUCUGCUACACGGGAGCCACCAUACAGAGUACCUAGGGAUGAUUGGGAAGAAAAAAGGCACUUUAGAAGAGAUAGUUUUGAUGAUCGUGGUCCUAGUCUCAACCCAGUGCUUGAUUAUGACCAUGGAAGUCGUUCUCAAGAAUCUGGUUAUUAUGACAGAAUGGAUUAUGAAGAUGACAGAUUAAGAGAUGGAGAAAGGUGUAGGGAUGAUUCUUUUUUUGGUGAGACCUCGCAUAACUAUCAUAAAUUUGACAGUGAGUAUGAGAGAAUGGGACGUGGUCCUGGCCCCUUACAAGAGAGAUCUCUCUUUGAGAAAAAGAGAGGCGCUCCUCCAAGUAGCAAUAUUGAAGACUUCCAUGGACUCUUACCGAAGGGUUAUCCCCAUCUGUGCUCUAUAUGUGAUUUGCCAGUUCAUUCUAAUAAGGAGUGGAGUCAACAUAUCAAUGGAGCAAGUCACAGUCGUCGAUGCCAGCUUCUUCUUGAAAUCUACCCAGAAUGGAAUCCUGACAAUGAUACAGGACACACAAUGGGUGAUCCAUUCAUGUUGCAGCAGUCUACAAAUCCAGCACCAGGAAUUCUGGGACCUCCACCUCCCUCAUUUCAUCUUGGGGGACCAGCAGUUGGACCAAGAGGAAAUCUGGGUGCUGGAAAUGGAAACCUGCAAGGACCUAGACACAUGCAGAAAGGCAGAGUGGAAACUAGCAGAGUUGUUCACAUCAUGGAUUUUCAACGAGGGAAAAACUUGAGAUACCAGCUAUUACAGCUGGUAGAACCAUUUGGAGUCAUUUCAAAUCAUCUGAUUCUAAAUAAAAUUAAUGAGGCAUUUAUUGAAAUGGCAACCACAGAGGAUGCUCAGGCCGCAGUGGAUUAUUACACAACCACACCAGCGUUAGUAUUUGGCAAGCCAGUGAGAGUUCAUUUAUCCCAGAAGUAUAAAAGAAUAAAGAAACCUGAAGGAAAGCCAGAUCAGAAGUUUGAUCAAAAGCAAGAGCUUGGACGUGUGAUACAUCUCAGCAAUUUGCCGCAUUCUGGCUAUUCUGAUAGUGCUGUUCUCAAGCUUGCUGAGCCUUAUGGGAAAAUAAAGAAUUACAUAUUGAUGAGGAUGAAAAGUCAGGCUUUUAUUGAGAUGGAGACAAGAGAAGAUGCAAUGGCAAUGGUUGACCAUUGUUUGAAAAAAGCCCUUUGGUUUCAGGGGAGAUGUGUGAAGGUUGACCUGUCUGAGAAAUAUAAAAAACUGGUUCUGAGGAUUCCAAACAGAGGCAUUGAUUUACUGAAAAAAGAUAAAUCCCGAAAAAGAUCUUACUCUCCAGAUGGCAAAGAAUCUCCAAGUGAUAAGAAAUCCAAAACUGAUGGUUCCCAGAAGACUGAGAGUUCAACCGAAGGUAAAGAACAAGAAGAGAAGUCCGGUGAAGAUGGUGAGAAAGACACAAAGGAUGACCAGACAGAGCAGGAACCUAAUAUGCUUCUUGAAUCUGAAGAUGAGCUACUUGUAGAUGAAGAAGAAGCAGCAGCACUGCUAGAAAGUGGCAGUUCAGUGGGAGACGAGACCGAUCUUGCUAAUUUAGGUGAUGUGGCUUCUGAUGGGAAAAAGGAACCAUCAGAUAAAGCUGUGAAAAAAGAUGGAAGUGCUUCAGCAGCAGCAAAGAAAAAGCUUAAAAAGGUGGACAAGAUCGAGGAACUUGAUCAAGAAAACGAAGCAGCGUUGGAAAAUGGAAUUAAAAAUGAGGAAAACACAGAACCAGGUGCUGAAUCUUCUGAGAACGCUGAUGAUCCCAACAAAGAUACAAGUGAAAACGCAGAUGGUCAAAGUGAUGAGAACAAGGACGACUAUACAAUCCCAGAUGAGUAUAGAAUUGGACCAUAUCAGCCCAAUGUUCCUGUUGGUAUAGACUAUGUGAUACCUAAAACAGGGUUUUACUGUAAGCUGUGUUCACUCUUUUAUACAAAUGAAGAAGUUGCAAAGAAUACUCAUUGCAGCAGCCUUCCUCAUUAUCAGAAAUUAAAGAAAUUUCUGAAUAAAUUGGCAGAAGAACGCAGACAGAAGAAGGAAACUUAAGAUGUGCAAGGAGAUUUAAUGAUUUCAAAGAAAAUAAUGGUUCUUUGUUUUUAAUGUUAACCUUUUUUAAAUACAAUACUGAUAGUUAGAAGAAAACUAUUGUACUCUUUUGUUUUAGUGGAGAAAUAAUAGAUGUCUGUUCAUGUGUUAAGUGUUAUAGCAAAAAAAAUACACAUAUGGUUAAGUUAAUGAAUAGUUUUUGUUUUAUCAGAAUGGCAACAGACAGAAGUACUUUGUAGAGAUUGACUUCCUAAGCUACUUAAGACAACUUGCACCACUAAGAAAAAAAUGUAGAACCAUUUGGAAAAAUGAAAUUUAGUAGUUCCAAGUUUCAAAGAAAUGUCAACAUUUUAUUCCAUUCAAUAAAGAACAAAACCAAUAGUGUUUUUAUUACUUUCAUCUGAAACAUUCCAUGUUUUAAUCUGAGCCUUGCAGACUUUCAUUUGGAGUUUGAACCCGUUUUGGUUGCAUUUCAUUUUUGGAGAACUUAAUUAACGUGAGAUUGGCAAUUGAAAUGCAGGUGCAGUUUUCUGUUAAUGUCAUGCUGUUGUUUAGGUAAUAAGAAAUAUUAAGUAAUUGGCUUUAGAUUUUGUAAUUUUUUUCCCUGAGUUCCUGCUAGAUUUCGUAUUCUAGUAGUCAAUGUAUUUUCAGUGAAAUGCAAAAAUAUUCCCGUUAUCUUUGACCAGUAUUAAUUUUUGAGAUCUUACUGCUUGUCACUUGAAUCCCGUGAUUGUCAUACAUCUCUGGUAUAAGCAACAUUUGAUUUUUGAAGUGUGUAGACCAUCUCUUCAUAUUUUCAAGAUGUAAUUUUACAUUUCUGCAUUUUUAAAACAGUUUGGCCAUAAUCCUAGAUGCACGCUUCUAAUUCAUGUACCUGCACAUGUGACCUUUGUGAACAGAAAUUUGCAUGUAUAAUUUGUGUUUACUUGUAACUUUCUGGUUAUAUACUGCUUAUAUCUGUGGAUUCAAGUUACUGAAGUGAAUACCAAUAAAAAGAAAACCCUAGGCCAUGUUAAUUGGUUAUACAUGUUUGGAAUGUUAACCAACGUAUUUGUCAGUUGUGGUUUUUAUUCGCUCUUAAACUUUGUGCAUGCUUUAACAAUUUAUUACUUUUAAAUCUAGAGUGAAUUCUAAAGACUGCCGCUAAAGAUCUGAGUUUUAAAAAUGUUGUUGCUGGUGGAUUUCUUGUUCCUGUUACAUAACUAAAAGUGAGGCCAUUUGUGGUUUUUAAAAACCUUAUGAAUUAAAAAUGCUACAGGUGAACAAACAGAAGCUUAUGUUUAGAGAUAUUGAUGACUUAACAGUACAAUUGGAAGUAAUACGGAUGAGCAAGAAUUAGUUCUGCAGCUUUUCAAAAUAAUUACGUAGAGACUCUUGGUAUAUUGGAUUAUCUGUUGUAAACAAUUUUUUUUUCUUCCCUGACACAGGGUCUCACUCUGUCACCCAGACUGGAGUGCAGUGGCACAGUUCUCUGCAACCUCAGCCUUUGGGCUCAAAUGACCCUCCUACCUCAGUCUCCUGAGUAGCUGGGACUACAGGCUCAUGCCACUAUACCUGGCUAGUUUUUGGUUUUUUUGUAUAGAUGGGGCUUUGCCAUGUUGCCCAGGUUGAUCUUGAAUUCCUGGGCCCAAGUGAUCUGCUCGCUUCAGCCUCCCAAAGUGCUGGGACUGUAGGCAUGAGCCACCAUCCCUGGCCAAGAAACAAAGUUUUAAUUUCAAAAAAAUCUACAAAAACAGGAUAGGCAUUGUCUUUCAAAUGUUCAGACCCCAGUUUAUUAAAGGAUACUUCAAAUAGUUGGCUAAAUUUUAUGAUCUCUCCCGUUGAAAAGUAGGUGAUGAUUUUAAUGUGACAUGCACAAAAAAUCCUUGCCAGUUUACUUCUGCAAUUUAAUUUUAGCCUUUACUAAUUACCCACUUCUGUUUAAUUCCAAUUUUUAACAGCAGGUACAUAAAGCAUUAUGUGCACAAUGGAGUUCUUCAGUGUUUCCUUUCAGUGAUGGCUUUUUCAUAGCUUCAACUUUGUUGGAUUUAGCAAGUUGAAGGAAAGAAUGCUAUGUUUUUAAUACCUACAUUUGAGAGCAUUUAGAAAUCAGAAAUUAUAAUAAGCUGUUAGUGAUAAAUCUGUAACAGCCCUUCGAUUACGAGAAAACCUCUUUUUAGUAGGAAUGUUUCCACUCAUGUUUGCUGUAAAGUUUAAGAACAUUUUUCCUACGGCUAUGUCAGCCCUUAGUUUAAUCUUACAUUAUCCUACAAAAGUGAAUGAAACUUCUAGAAGUACCUUGA